GUCAGAGCUGGAGGGCCGGGCACCGCGGCCAUGGAGGGUCAACGCUGGCUGCCGCUGGAGGCCAAUCCCGAGGUCACCAACCAGUUUCUUAAACAAUUAGGUCUACAUCCUAACUGGCAAUUCGUUGAUGUAUAUGGAAUGGAUCCUGAACUCCUUAGCAUGGUACCAAGACCAGUCUGUGCAGUCUUACUUCUCUUUCCUAUUACAGAAAAGUAUGAAGUAUUCAGAACAGAAGAGGAAGAAAAAAUAAAAUCUCAGGGACAAGAUGUUACAUCAUCAGUAUAUUUCAUGAAGCAAACAAUCAGCAAUGCCUGUGGAACAAUUGGACUGAUUCAUGCUAUUGCAAACAAUAAAGACAAGAUGCACUUUGAAUCUGGAUCAACCUUGAAAAAAUUCCUGGAGGAAUCUGUGUCAAUGAGCCCUGAAGAACGAGCCAGAUACCUGGAGAACUAUGAUGCCAUCCGAGUUACUCAUGAGACCAGUGCCCAUGAAGGUCAGACUGAGUCCUCCUCGCCAUCCUCAUCACAGCCUCAUUCUAGCCACUGCAGAACGAAGGCCUCAUCAUUGUGUCACCAUGCAUCCCUGCCCUGGGUCAAACGUAACCAUGUAGGCCCUGCAAAGGCUACCAGUCCAUCUCUCCGUCUUCGUCGCUGGCGACCCUUCUUACGUCUACCAUCUUUGGGUCUCCAUUCUGUUGCACCAAGUAUAGAUGAGAAAGUAGAUCUUCAUUUUAUUGCAUUAGUUCAUGUAGAUGGGCAUCUCUAUGAAUUAGACCUUCUCGAGUUUUAAAAAAGCCAAAUAAACAACAAAAAAGAGAAGUUCUUUUCAGUAAUUCUAGAUACCGUGAGUUUUGGUUCUAUUACCUCUCAUUUGCUGUCUAUAUAUUACCUUGUCACAUUAAUUUUAAGUUGUAUAAAGAUAGAAGAUUUUGAAAGAACACAGAUUGUGACUGUAAAUGUGAUCCAUAAAAUUUAGGUGGAUUUUGUGUUUGGAAUAUUAGCAACAGAUCGCAUACUUUAUUAAAAAGAAAUGGCCCUAUCAAAGGGGACAAGGAAAAGAAAGAACAUAGUAUUUAUAAAAAUGUGCAACCCUGAGCGUUGUCUACAAUACUAGAGUGAUUUGAGGAGUAAUAAAACUUAAAUGAGAAGAAGUCAUUAUUUUGGUAGUAUAUAAUGGACCUCCAGGACAGUUUUGAAGAUGUGCCUUGCUAAUUGAGUCUACAAAAUCUGCAGAGAUAAAGUAUAACAGUGAUUGGGGACUUCAGAUGUCUGGGUGGUUGCUGGAAGCAGAUUUUCUACUCUGAAUUGUGAAUAGUAAAUAAUAACUAGUGGAAGAGGAAAUAAAGAGUGCUGGGACUUAACAGACACAUUCUGUUAACUUCAAGAAAGUAGAUUUGGCCAGAGCAAACAUAUGUAGGAUUCAUAACCAGAGACUAUAAAUCUGAUUGUGACUUUCAGAAUGAGAGACUUACAGAGCAAACAAUAACAUCUAAAAUAUAUUUAAACCAAAAGAAAACCUCUCUAAUGAUCUCAAUGGGAAGGAAAGAGUUAUCUUAAAAAAAAACUCGGUUUUACUAGUUAGAGAGCUGUCUUGGCUCAGAGGCUAAAAGGGCAGUUAGAAGGAAGGACAUAUAUCAAGGGUAAGCUACAUAUGAAGAAUGAUGCUCUUUUGGAGCAUGCCAAGAUCAACACAAAAGGAUUUUAAAAUUGGUUUGAAGUAAGAACUUCAUAAAACAAAGGCAGAACUACUGAGGUCUUGUUUGGUUUAGAUAUUCUUUAUCAAGAAGAAUGAUCUGAUGGAAAAUUAGAAGCCUACUGGAAAUUAGAUUUUUUAAAUGAGUUUAAAUAAUUUCAGAGUGGUAAAGAAUAGCCAUAAUCUUUGAGAUGUCAGAGCAAUAAUAGGUACAUUACAAAGAUGGACAGUUGCUGAUUCAUUGCAAAGGAAACUGGCAGUAACUCUGAUGCAGAUCUAAUAAAUUCAAAAGGAAUAUUGAGCAAGAAGAGUAUUGAGUUAGUGAGUAGAAAAUAAUGAUUAAGAGAUUAGCACUGGGCACAGUGGUGUGUUCCUGUAGUCCCACUUUCUGUAGUGGGAAGCUGAAGCACGAUUGCCUGAGCCCAGGAGUUUGAGGCUACAGUGUGCUAUGAUUGCACCUGUGAACAGCCACUACACUUCUGCCUGGGUGACAUGGCAAGACGUCAUCUCUUAAAAAAAAAAGAAAAGAAGACACUAUAUAACUUUUAAGAAAGAAGUCAUUUCAAAGUUCAAUUUGCUCUCUGUGGGUUCUUGCAUUGGUAGAUUCAACCAACUGUGGAUUGAAAGUAUUAGAAAAUAAAUACCAAUACAACAAUAAAAAACAAAUUUUGAAAACAACAUAACAACUAUUUACAUAGCAUUUAUAUUGUAUUAUGUAUGAUAAGUAAUCUAGAGAUGAUUUAAAGUAUUUGGAAUUGUGUAGGUUAUAUGCAAAUACUAUACCAUUUAGGUAGAGUAUGUCAAGGGGCUUGAACAUCUCAAAAUUUUGGUAUGAGAUGGGGCCGGUGUCCUGGAACCAGUCCCCCACAGAUAUGGAGAGAUGACUGUAACUUUAUUUUUAAAAAUAAGGCUGUAUGAUUGUAGACAUUGUGCAAGUUAAUUUCUAUAGGAUAUCUAUAUUUAACAGAGAAUGGUGGUAGUCUUUAAUGUAUUAAUUCCCUACUCUAAUAAAUUGUAAGGUUAACCAAUGAAAA